AGCAACCCAGAUGAGCAAAACUUAAAUAUACUUUAGCUUCUUUUGUAAAGCAAAGGAUAAUGUUAAACUGUUAGUCUCUCUUGGCUUUACAGAAAAGAUUUGCUGAGAUAUAUUACUCUAAAACUUUUAUGAAAAGCUAUCUUUCAAAUGAUUCCUCCAUGUGAAAAUGCCCCCCACAUAAUAUACCAUGAGUCUCAGAGAGGCACAAGAGAUAGGGAUAUUGCAAAGAGGCUGCAAUAUCCUUCACGACAGGAUCUCAACUCCAAAUGGAAAAAAAGUGUUCUGCAACCUCCACAAUGUAAAAUGAAAGUUAAUGUAUGGGAAAUAAAGCCUCCUGAUUUUAGCUACAAACUGUAUACAUCUUUGAGAAUUCCAGAAAGAUCAUCAAAACCAAUUAAGGAAGAAAAAAGGAGGAAAAAAAUCAGUUUUCCAGAAACAAUGCUUCACUUGCCCAGCAUAAGGAAUCAUCCUAAGGAGGUUACAGCUCCUAAAUUUAUAACUACAUUUCCACAUCUGGAUUUACAAAAAGCAAAGUUAAUGUUUGUGAAGAGUGGACAAUAUCCAAGGGGUGUAUAUGUCAAUCCCAAACCACAUGACUUUCGACAGUACCAACCUGGUUUACCAAACUUUGAGACAACUUAUGAAAAGGACCCCUUUGGAUUAAAAUUUAAAUCACAACACUUAAGUACAGUACAUGGGUACCAGUUACCGAAAGAUGAUAAACAGAAGACUAGUACAGAAAGAUUUAUCACCCACAAGCAUUGUGAAUGCACCUGGGAUUCAAAACUAAUUUUGACGAAAGCCCCAUGGCCUGUUAGAUCUGCUUCAUAUACAAGACAUAGAAGGCAGCGUGAUGCAUACAGUGCAUUUAUGGAUCGUGUGGAAGAAAAGUUUACAAAGAUAUGCAAGAGCAGGUGUUGGUGUCCAGAGGAGAAAUGGAAGAAACAGGGGCAAAAAGCUCAGAUAGCUGAUGGACCAAAACAGCAUAGGGCUUCCUGAACUCUGGCCUGAAUGUUCAUCUCCCGUGCAUUUCCCAGUGAGAACAUUGAUGAAUUCUGGCACCUUCCUGGAUUCUACAGAAAUCUGCACUCUCCCAGAGGCAUGAGAAAGUGCUAAAACAACAAAUGAAAGUUGCAUAAUUUGAAAUUCCCUUGUUACCACAGGGAUCAGAAUCCAAUCAUAAGGCUUUUGAUUUAGUUUGUGAAAGUUAGAUCUUGCAACUAUGAGUGGAAAUGCUGAUAAUGUGCUUUCUGUUAAUGUCCAAAGUUAAAGAUGCUCUAGUCUCAGGUAAAGCUAAUGUGAGACAAACAACAAUAAUGCUUACUAAUUUUGACCACCAUGUUUCUCUAAGGCCAAAGAUUGCAAAUUUUAUCUGUUUGCCUCCUUCAUAGAAAUAAGAAUUCUCUGGAUAUAGCAUAUAUUCUACUAAAGGAUGACUGUUAUGCUGUGUGGGAAAGUAGUAGUUAAAAAUCAAAUAUUUUUACUUUAAAAAAUAGAGAACAAGGUAGCAACCAGAAUUGAAGUCACUGAAAUAUAAAUGGGGCACUUUCCCAGAGGAUGUCAUCCAAAGACAAAAAAAUAGGAAAGUUUAAUUCAUGACACAGUGAAGUUCUUCUACGGUUUAAAUUGUUCCUAGAAAUAGAUUUUAUUUUCAGGAAUCAUAGGAUACCAGAUGGUUAGUGAUAGUGUUUAUUUCUGAAAAAAAAAAGAAGAAAAAGAAAAGAAAAGAAAAAGAGUAUAUGUAUGAGCUUUGUGUUCACAUAUACAAGGUGGCAUAGGUUGAAAUAAUCAACAUUUAUUUAGUAUGUUUAUGGCAUAUUGAAAUCAAUAUUUGAAUCUUCAUUUUUCAGUUUUUUCUAAUACACUUUAAGAAGCUUCUCUGAGACACUCAAGUAUAUCAAAAGAGAGAAGAUCUCCAAGUAACAGAAAUAAUAAAUGUCCUUCUUAAAGAACACCAGGCUUGGAGAAUUUAUAGUUCCAACUAGAAGGAAAGGUCUGUCUUUUAACAUGUUAAAAUAAUUUUCUAAAUUUUUGUUUAAAUAUUUUGAGGGAAAGAAAACAAAUGACUUGAAACUUCUUUGCUUCUGAUCAAGAUUUGAUGAUUAUAAUUGAAAAUUAAUAAAAGGGGAGGGUAGGAUUUAAUGCUAUUGCCAGUUUUAUCAAAUGGAUUAUCCUAUCACCUUUCCAAUUUCACUAUGAAAACUACUGAAAUAAAGGCAAGUACGUAUUUAA